AAUCCCAGGGCGGAGGCCUCGCGCAAAACCCAGGCGCCGCGGCUCCGCGCUCCGGCUGAGGGUCCGCGCCGCCGCCCGCCCGCUCCUUCCCGCUCGGCCGCGGCCUCAGGGACGGAUACUCCAGCGCGCGGUUCCAACCGAGGCCCGUGGCGGGUUUAGCCCCACGAAGAUGAACUGGGCACCCGCAACGUGCUGGGCUCUGCUACUGGCGGCCGCCUUCCUCUGCGACAGCGGCGCAGCCAAGGGCGGCCGCGGAGGUGCGCGGGGCAGUGCCCGGGGAGGGGUCCGCGGGGGUGCGCGCGGGGCCUCGAGGGUGCGCGUGAGGCCGGCGCAGCGCUACGGUGCCCCGGGCUCCUCCCUGCGCGUGGCUGCCGCCGGGGCGGCAGCCGGGGCGGCGGCGGGAGCGGCCGCGGGCCUGGCGGCGGGCUCGGGCUGGAGAAGGGCCGCGGGACCCGGGGAACGCGGCCUGGAGGACGAGGAGGACGGGGUGCCCGGAGGCAACGGGACAGGCCCCGGCAUCUACAGCUACCGGGCGUGGACUUCGGGCGCUGGACCCACGCGCGGCCCGCGUCUCUGUCUCGUGCUGGGCGGCGCCCUCGGAGCCCUGGGGCUGCUGCGGCCCUAGGCCUGGCUGGGCUCGGGGACCACAUCUGGCCCCCGGCCCGCGCCAUCCCCCAGGAUCCUCCGGCCUGGGCUCCCCCUUCCUCCCUUGCCCACGGUCUUGGAGCCCCACUGGGUGCAGGAGCUGCUGGCUGUCCCUGUGGACCCGCCAUCCACCGUCCUGCCCACGCCGCCUCAGCCUGCCACCUCCCACCUAGAGGAGACCAUGGGCCCUGCCCCACCCACUCCAGGAUGUUAGGGUCCCCUCAGCCAAAAAGGCAGCUGCCUGUGGCUCCUGUACCAACCGCCCAGCCACGCUCCAUCGCCGCCCAAAGGGAGGUGCCAAGGCCAGGAACCCAAGCCACCCCGGCUCCCCUCGCCUGCCCAGGGGCCGUGGUGACUCACGGGCAGGGAGGCGACAUCAGGCUGGUUCUGCCACUGAGCCCCUGAGGAAUCUGACCCUCCCCAAAAGAAGCAGUGAAAUGGACCAAAGGACUUAAGAAUUUGGGGGGAAGUGAGGGAAAAACGUUAGGUGCUAACCACCUGCCCAGAAGAGUGGAUCUCACAGCCCAGGAACAUUCCCAAGCAGGAAAACCGUCCGUCCGAGGAACGUCCAUCCUGGCUCUCUGCGGCUGGUGGGAAAACACACCCUGCCCUGAGGGGCUGUCCAGGCCUUCUCCCCCACACCCUCAGGCCGAGAUCCGUGAGAGACCCACUUUGCUCCAACAACUUGAAACAAGUCACUUUACCCUCCUUAGGACCCAUUUUGGGGGGGAAAAACCAACACAUUCCAGAGCUUUCCAAGUCCUUUGAACUUCAGGUUCACAUUCAGGGAUCACACAGUUCUGCCUGUUCUCAGGGCACAGCAACUGCCAAUCCCGCUGAAGAGGCCUCCCUGGGCACAGCACAGGCUGCACGGUGCACGCAUUUCCCUGAAGGCAGCCCCUUCUUCGGAAGCAGCUGUUCCAGGCCUCGGAACAGGGCCUGGGUAUCCGCGUGGUGGGCUGGCAGCUGACGGCCUGCUCAGUGGAGCCAGGAGCUAACUCAGACCCCAAAGCAAGCAGGGGGCCAGUGGCGGGGCCCAGCGCCCAGCAGGACACCCAUGCAAGAGGCUGAGCCCCCCAACAUCCAAGGACAGGAGAGACAUGGAGUGGCGCUGGACAGUCACGACAAGGACUUGCCUCCAGCACUGGACACACCUGUGUUAAGACCAGCCCUCUGCUUCCCAGUCCCGCCAGCCUGGGGCAUCCUCCAUGGGCUCAGCACUGAGAGGUCUUGGGUCUGCCACGUUCUCUAGCUCUCCAGUCACCCACUCAUCCAGGGUAGGAGGGGUUCUCCCUGCCCCCCGCCGUGGCCUUGGGAUCUCACCCUCUCCAUGUCCUGGGGACAGCCUCGCCCUCAGCCGGACUGCAUCCCUCCUGGGCCUGAGCCUCGGGACUCAGUGGACACCAAAGUCAAGACCAGCACCCACCACGGGCCCUGCCAGCCUCUGCCUUCCCCAGCUGGCCUGGGUUCUGGCCUGGGUGAGGAUCUGGAAGCUGUUGGCAGGACUCAACCAAGCACUGCUCUCUAGCUCCAGGGCACUAAGCCACAGGAGGCAGCGCCCUGCAGCCUCCCGUCCACACUGCCAGCAAUGCCCCUGGCCCAGUGAGCCCAGACGCUCCUCCACCCCUUCCAGACCAAGCUCAACGCCUCCAAGACCAGCAGGCCAAGGCCAAGCCCUGCCCCAGAUCCUCAUAGGCAGAGAAGCCCUUCUGACAUUUCCCCCAGGAGGCAGGGGGUGGUCUGAGUCUCCUCACAGCAGAGAGACCCACCGGAGCCCCCUCAACUUUGCAGAUGCCCACCUGGAAAAUGGGCUGAGCUGCACCAGACCCUCACACACCACAGCACUGCAAGCUGAUGGAAUGUUCCAGUUAUGAUGGACACUUCGUGAUCUGCAAUGACUGUUGAUUCAGCACAUUAGCAUCUGACACAGCCAACCUGAAUACUUCCUGCCCCAGGCGGUCAGGGUUAUGGCACGAUGCAGGUGGCACUCAGGGGCUAACUUCAGGCUGAUGAGUGUGUGGGGUAUGGGGCAGCAGAGGCAGCCAGCCAGCAAAGAGGGGCCACUGAGCACCAGGGCCCUGGUGGAGGCUGCUGUGGGACGGUCAGGCCACCACCGCAAAGAGGCAGCCGGAGCUUCUGCACAGGAUGUCCCUGGCCCCAGGUCCUGCAGCACCUUAGUCCAUACUACCAGCCCCACCCACCUUCCUUCCUCUUCCCUCUUCUAGGACACAGGCUGUGGACCCCUUCAGGUGCACUAUAAUGGGGCUGGAGGGGCCCCCACAUCUCUCAGCCCCACUAAUGCAGAAUCCCACUACCCGUGAGCUAGAAGGUGCUCAGAGGCCAGGGGUCUCUACUGCCCAUGCCGGGCGGCCUUCCAGUCAUUGCACAGCAAAGCCAUGUGCAGGGCGUCCCCCUCAACCCUGCCCUGAACAUGCCCCAGGGCACUGAGGGGCGAAGCCAGUGCUUGGGCUCUGCUGCUGGGAGUCUCUGGUCUGUGUCUGUGUGUGCCUGUAAGUGUGAAAUAAACCUCUCUGAUGGCA